UUCUUCCCCCGUUUUCCCUAAAAGAGUUGAUUUUUUUUCCCAGUCGAGACUCUUCCGAGCUGAAUAAUGCACCCGCUCGCUGAGCCAGUAUCCCGCGACCCCGCACUCUCGGACUGGCCCGGGCUGUCUCGGAUUCGCACCCUUUGGCCAAGCUGGGCCUGAACCCGGGUCCAAAUCUGGGACCAUACCCGGCCAUGCCUGAAACACAGGCGUCGGCCCUAGCCCGGGAACUGUGUUAGCCUUAUGUUCCCUGAGCUCUCGCAUAUGGUGGUAAAAUUUCUGUUAGAGCGGUGUUUCCAAAUACCCCCUGGGCAUUUGGUGUGCGGGAAUUCUCUUCAAGCGAAGAAGUCUGUGAACUUAAAAAAAAAAUUUUUUUCCUGCGUUCUUAACAACCCCCCACUACUCUGCCUCAUUUCCCAUUGUUCUUUGCUUUUUAAGUUCCUUGUUAAUUUUUUUAAAAGUUUAUUUAUGCAAAGGAAAAAUAUCGUUUAAUUUGUUCUAUUAUUUUAAUUCCUGGCUUUUGGAAACGGUUCAGAGACCACAAAACUGUCACCUGUUGUAAUAAGCAGAGGAGUGUUGUGUGUGCAUUUUAAUUGCCAGCAGAGCCGUAGUUUGGUGGGCGCCCUGAGCUCGGCUCCGGGAAAGAGCCCUUUGCAGCUUUCUUUGUGGCAGUCAUUUGCAAAGGGGUUUGGCUCUCAGCUACGGCGGAGGCAGAGGGGGCAGCAGCACCGCUUCCUUCUAUGCCGAUCCCGGGCGCAGGUCAGGAAGCCCAGACCUUGGACUGGGAUGGGAGAUUACCUACUCUCUGAGACUUUCUCUUGGGCUUUCGGUUUUUCUGUGCGAAAGUGGCUAGUUCGCUCCGCAGAGCGCGGAGCGCUGCGCAUCAGCCCAGCCUCAGACAUUUUCACGUUCCAAACGCGGACGUCUUCGUUUCAUUUGUCUUGGUUCUGGCGUGUUUAACCACGCAAUUAGUAAUCUCACUAAUUAUUCAGAUAGCUGGCGUUUUGCAAUCACUUUAAACCAGGGUCAGGAGUGUGAUUUAAGAAACAAACAAACUCCCACAGAUACGGAACUGAACCAAACCCAUCACGUCAAGGAUUUGAAAUUUUUUAACUCAAUAUUUGUUGGUCCCUCCGUCCAACCUCACUGCCUGCCAGACAAUUUAUUUAGCUUCGUGGAUUGAUCCCUCCUCCUUGUUUAGUUAAUUCAACAAAGACUUUUUGCAAUCUGUUUGGAGUUUGUCUGAUGCCGUGGAAAAGUAGCUGAUGAUUUAUUUGGUUGCUUUUCGAUUUCUGUCUUCAGCCCUUCUUUCUCCUCCUUUCAGCGGGGAUGUCAGCUGUUAUUACUUCCUAUUGAUCCCUUUGCAAAGUGAGAAGUGAACUAAAAUUAAUGUCAAUUCCACUGCUCGGAUCAAUAGCUGGAGUUAUUUUAAUCUGGAUUUGCACGAAGUGCUAAAUUAAAAAAAAUCAGCAUAGAGGCAGAAAAGUAACAGUUACUUACUUUCCCUUUGCCGGGUUCUUCACAGUCACCCAAAUGCUCCAUCAAGCUGAUUAUCUUACAAUCCAUAUUUUUUUAAUUAAGAGGGUCAGUUAGUUUUCUUAUUUUGGGUUCUGUGUUUAAACCCAUGACAUUUUGACAUUGGGAGUGUAUUAACUAUAGAUUUUCAUAAUGACUGUGGUCAGCUGAAGCCUCAUCUAUACAAGUUGUUAAUGUGAGGAGAGGGUAAGAAAGAAAAGGGAAAAGAAAAAAAAGAAAAAAAGCACUCCCCCCUCCCCCAUGGAGACCAACGCCCACGCAAUGAAGUAAAAGAGAUGUGGCCUGGAAAAAUAUUGUUGAUUUAUUUUCAGUGUAAUGAAGUUUUCAAAUGAAUAACCAGGGUUGAGUGAUUCACCAGGUUCUGUUGGAGUGUCCGGUGCUGUCACCAGAUUCCUAAUUUAUGAAACUCAUUUAAGAUAAUGAGGUGAUCUAGGAAGUAAAAAUAGCAAGUGAAUCCUGGGGGGGGUCGUAUUUUGAGGGGGAAACAUUCCUCCCUUCACAUUUCUUUUCUCCAGUUUUCCUCAUAUAAUAUUGCUUGUUGAUAGAUAAGUAGCUAUUUCUGUUGUGAAGAGCUGCUUAGAACCCUUGGAACAGCCCUAGACCCACUUUCAGAGCGUCCAUGUUGUAUGACCAUUAAUCUGACUAGAAAACAGCCAAGAACAGGAUUCCCAGACUUGUCAGCCUAACUGGCUGUCCUUGGCAGAUCAUUCCCUGCACUGCUAUAACUUGACAGGAAAGUUAUUUAAAAUUUGGAAGAGAGAAAAAUCCGUUAAUGUGAGAUACAUAAUCUGGUAAUUUAGCAAUGAUGUCUAUAAGGAAAGAUGCCAAAUGAGGAAGCAGUCUGAUGGUGUCCACUCAUCUUCCCAAUUAAUAACAGUCAUUGACAUGUCUGCUACAGGAUGGGAGAAGGAAAUACUCUCUUUGCACUGCAUUAAGCCAGGAGGAUUCAUCUACCGUUUAACUGAUGUUUCUCUGUUUGAGGGAAUACCAAAGAUACUCCAGGUGGGCUUUUUAAAAGGGACGAGGUAGAUUUUAUUUCUGAUAUGACUCUCAAUUUAAAGGUAUAAUUUGUAGCAGACGGUGAUUUUUGGUUAUGCUUUGAGUUUCACUAAGUUUCUAUUUCGUGUAUAUUUUUGACACUAAUAAGUCUUGGUAUUCAUCUUAUAUUGUCCCGGCUUUUGAUAUAUAGCCCUUCUCCCAGCCCCCACUCAAAAUACACUUUGGAAUGGAACCACUGACUAUGAAAAUGUACAACCUAAAUUUACAAGGGAAACUGAAAGAAGUCUCUCCGAACUCCAAUUUGUUCCGGGGGCCUUUAUUGGACAUCAGCUCUGACUGGGCCAAUAAGCAGAGCAAAAUAAGUCAGAAAUUUUGUUAACAUUUUGUUCUAAAUGUUAAUGGCAAAUCCAAGGCAGUUUACAAAUCUACUUAAGAGUGAGUGCAUUAGUAACUAAAAUCACCGAUCUGUUCUUUGCUGCCCUUAGAAGACAGAUGCUUCUAGAGAGCGUAUGCCAAAGGCACCCAUUAUGGUUUUAAGUGUUGUCAGAGACGCCAGGCAUUUUAUUGAUGAAGGUUUUGUUCCUUCUCAGAAAAGAGAAAUAGAAAGCCCAUGUGAUUAGAGAGAGGUGUGCCUCAAAAUAAAUGUUAAUGCUGUUUGUUCAUAUAGCACUUUUUUCUGGAAACAGUCUUAGAUGAUACAUGAAGAUGUGUGUGUGUGUGUAUAUGCCAAUGUGUAUCUUUUAUCCAUGUGUAUACUUUGUACUAACUAAUAUGUACAAGUGUUCCUGGUCUAGAUGAACUUGAAUUAGGGAUAUUUCAGUAUCAGGGUGUUGUUAGGGGAGAUGAAGAGAGGAUGCAUAUGUGGGGAAUCGUAUAGGUAGAAUGUGGUCUCUGAACAUCAGGCCUGCCAUGAGUGGUGGAUGCAGGUGGAAGCACUUUAAAACAUAGACCCCCACUUAAUCUACUGGAUGGCUUGGCCUUCCAAAGCUCAUUUGUUCAGAGAAUAUCGUAUUUGGAGGUUUUAUGAUAUUUUUUUCUUUGCUGGGCUCAGGCGCAUUUCACCCAGAACGUGUAGGGACCAAAGUCAGCUACGCGUACAUCACAGUCUUAGGAGGGAAUGAUUCCCCAGUAAUAUUCCCUGCCCUGACCCAAAGUGCUGGUUGGCCUCCCUCCCAGGGAAGACUGCUUCUUGCGUAACGCCGGCCACAGAAAGAGACUCCGAUGGACUUACACCGGGCAGCCUUCAAGAUGGAGAACUCAUCCUACCUUCCCAACCCUCUGGCAUCCCCAGCACUGAUGGUCCUGGCAUCCACGGCUGAGGCCAGCCGUGAUGCUUCCAUCCCUUGUCAGCAGCCACGACCCUUUGGUGUACCUGUCUCAGUUGACAAGGACGUGCAUAUUCCUUUCACCAACGGUUCCUAUACCUUUGCCUCUAUGUACCAUCGGCAAGGUGGGGUGCCAGGCACUUUUGCCAAUCGUGAUUUCCCCCCUUCUCUACUACACCUCCACCCUCAAUUUGCUCCCCCAAAUCUAGAUUGCACCCCAAUCAGUAUGCUGAAUCAUAGUGGUGUGGGGGCUUUCCGGCCCUUUGCCUCCACCGAGGACCGGGAGAGCUAUCAGUCAGCCUUUACGCCGGCCAAGCGACUUAAGAACUGCCAUGACACAGAGUCUCCCCACUUGCGCUUCUCAGAUGCAGAUGGCAAGGAAUAUGACUUUGGGACACAGCUGCCAUCUAGCUCCCCCGGUUCACUAAAGGUUGAUGACACUGGGAAGAAGAUUUUUGCUGUCUCUGGCCUCAUUUCUGAUCGGGAAGCCUCAUCUAGCCCAGAGGAUCGGAAUGACAGAUGUAAGAAGAAAGCAGCGGCAUUGUUCGACAGCCAGGCCCCAAUUUGCCCCAUCUGCCAGGUCCUGCUGAGGCCCAGUGAGCUGCAGGAGCAUAUGGAGCAGGAACUGGAGCAGCUAGCCCAACUGCCCUCGAGCAAGAAUUCCCUUCUGAAGGAUGCCAUGGCUCCAGGCACCCCAAAGUCCCUCCUGUUGUCUGCUUCCAUCAAGAGGGAAGGAGAGUCUCCAACGGCAUCACCCCACUCAUCUGCCACCGAUGACCUCCACCAUUCAGACAGAUACCAGACCUUUCUGCGAGUACGAGCCAACCGGCAGACCCGACUGAAUGCUCGGAUUGGGAAAAUGAAACGGAGGAAGCAAGAUGAAGGGCAGGUAUGUCCCCUGUGCAACCGCCCCCUGGCAGGAUCGGAGCAGGAGAUGAGUAGGCAUGUGGAGCAUUGCCUUUCUAAGAGGGAAGGCUCCUGCAUGGCUGAGGAUGAUGCUGUGGACAUCGAGCAUGAGAACAACAACCGCUUUGAGGAGUAUGAGUGGUGUGGACAGAAGCGGAUACGGGCCACCACUCUCCUGGAAGGUGGCUUCCGAGGCUCUGGCUUCAUCAUGUGCAGCGGCAAAGAGAACCCGGACAGUGAUGCUGACUUGGAUGUGGAUGGGGAUGACACUCUGGAGUAUGGGAAGCCACAAUACACAGAGGCUGAUGUCAUCCCCUGCACAGGCGAGGAGCCUGGUGAAGCCAAGGAGAGAGAGGCACUUCGGGGCGCAGUCCUAAAUGGCGGCCCUCCCAGCACGCGCAUCACACCUGAGUUCUCUAAAUGGGCCAGUGAUGAGAUGCCAUCCACCAGCAAUGGUGAAAGCAGCAAGCAGGAGGCCAUGCAGAAGACCUGCAAGAACAGCGACAUCGAGAAAAUCACCGAAGAUUCAGCUGUGACCACGUUUGAGGCUCUGAAGGCUCGGGUCAGAGAACUUGAACGGCAGCUAUCUCGUGGGGACCGUUACAAAUGCCUCAUCUGCAUGGACUCGUACUCGAUGCCCCUAACGUCCAUCCAGUGUUGGCACGUGCACUGCGAGGAGUGCUGGCUGCGGACCCUGGGUGCCAAGAAGCUCUGCCCUCAGUGCAACACGAUCACAGCGCCCGGAGACCUGCGGAGGAUCUACUUGUGAGCUAUCUGCCCCAGGCAGGCCUCGCCUCCAGCAGCCCCACCUGCCCCCAGCCUCUGUGACAGUGACCGUCUCCCUUUGUACAUACUUGCACACAGGUUCCCCAUGUACAUACAUGCACAUACUCAAACAUGCGUACACACACACACAUUUACACACGCAGGACUCUGGAGCCAGAGUAGAGGCUGUGGCCCAGGCACUACCUGCUGGCUCCCACCUAUGGUUUGGGGGCCAUACCUGUUCCAGCUCUGUUCCCAGGGUGGGGCAGGGAGGUGGGGGUUGGGGGAGUAGUGGGGCACGGCUCCUAAGAUCCAGCCCCCAUACUGACAGACGGACAGACAGACAUGCAAACACCAGACUGAAGCACAUGUAAUAUAGACCGUGUAUGUUUACAAUGUUGUGUAUAAAUGGGACAACUCCUCGCCCUCUACCUGUCCCCUCCCCCUUUGGUUGUAUGAUUUUCUUCUUUUUUAAGAACCCCUGGAAGCAGCGCCUCCUUCAGGGUUGGCUGGGAGCUCGGCCCAUCCACCUCUUGGGGUACCUGCCUCUCUCUCUCCUGUGGUGUCCCUUCCCUCUCCCAUGUGCUCGGUGUUCAGUGGUGUAUAUUUCUUCUCCCAGACAUGGGGCACACGCCCCAAGGGACAUGAUCCUCUCCUUAGUCUUAGCUCAUGGGGCUCUUUAUAAGGAGUUGGGGGGUAGAGGCAGGAAAUGGGAACCGAGCUGAAGCAGAGGCUGAGUUAGGGGGCUAGAGGACAGUGCUCCUGGCCACCCAGCCUCUGCUGAGAACCAUUCCUGGGAUUAGAGCUGCCUUUCCCAGGGAAAAAGUGUCGUCUCCCCGACCCUCCCGUGGGCCCUGUGGUGUGAUGCUGUGUCUGUAUAUUCUAUACAAAGGUACUUGUCCUUUCCCUUUGUAAACUACAUUUGACAUGGAUUAAACCAGUAUAAACAGUUG